GGUGGCAGCGGCAGCGGAGGAGGAAGCUGAGCAGGGCGGCGGCGGCGGUGGAACCUGCGGGGCUGGGGCGCGCGCCAUGGGCCGCCUGCACUGCACUGAGGACCCGGUGCCGGAGGCCGUGGGCGGCGACAUGCAGCAGCUGAACCAGCUGGGCGCGCAGCAGUUCUCAGCCCUGACAGAGGUGCUUUUCCACUUCCUAACUGAGCCAAAAGAGGUGGAAAGAUUUCUGGCUCAGCUCUCUGAAUUUGCCACCACCAAUCAGAUCAGUCUUGGCUCCCUCAGAAGCAUCGUGAAAAGCCUCCUUCUGGUUCCAAAUGGUGCUUUGAAGAAGAGUCUCACAGCCAAGCAGGUCCAGGCGGAUUUCAUAACUCUGGGUCUUAGUGAGGAGAAAGCCACUUACUUUUCUGAAAAGUGGAAGCAGAAUGCUCCCACCCUUGCUCGAUGGGCCAUAGGUCAGACUCUGAUGAUUAACCAGCUCAUAGAUAUGGAGUGGAAAUUUGGAGUGACAUCUGGGAGCAGCGAAUUGGAGAAAGUGGGAAGUAUAUUUUUACAACUAAAGUUGGUGGUUAAGAAAGGAAAUCAAACCGAAAAUGUGUAUAUAGUCAUUGCCAGCUGUGGAGUAGCUGUUCCACUGCCUUUCCUCUCCUGAAAGAUGGCACAAGGAGUGUUAGAAAGCCACUGGCAGGUUGGAGCCCCCACAGUUGAAGAGCCGUUUUGAAAAAGGGAAAGGGUGGGAACGGAAUGGCUGGGAUUGAAGAAGAAGGUUGACGAGCAAGAAGCUCUUGCCAUAGAAGUCACAUUGAACAUCCCGAAUGAUACCCUUUCAUCUCUUUGUGCCAUGGAGCUGUGCCAUUUGAACACUCACUCCCCUUUUUUUUCCUUUGGAGCAGAGAACCUUCUGCAUUCAAGUCUCUCAGUUCUUUAUUAUGAUCAGUUACCCAUCAAGAGCUGCUUAGAUGUAUUAAGCCAAAAAAGAAAAAAAAAAUCCUCCGGGUGGAAAUUAAUUUUCUUGGAUGAUUCUGUGGAGUUGGAAACAUUUAUCUGAAGCUGAAUUUUCUCUCCCCAGAAUUAACCUUGCCUCAGUUCUACAGCUUCCUGCACGAGAUGGAGCGAGUCAGAACCAGCAUGGAGUGUUUCUGCUGAUUUCUGUCCCUGCAUCUCCCCUGGCCCCGUUCCCUGCCCUCCUCCCUUCCCUGGGUGACUGCUCUGAGAGGCACUUCACUCACAGGCCUGUGGGAUGCUCCAUGGGGCCCUGCUGGCUCCAUGGGGCCCAGGUGCAAAGGGUUUCUGAAAAACAGCAGGAUUAAGUACUGAAAGAGCCCAACACAAUUACCCUGUAAACUCUCUGUUAGGGCAACCACCACCACCUGUCUUCCAGGACACAUUUUUAGAUACUCUGACAGGCCACUGCAUCUCAGAUUCAGGGGAGAAAAUAAGUUGUCACCUCCCCUUCAAAGUUCCAGAGUAAACAAAUGGUGCCAUCAUUCAAGAUAACAUGCUGAUCACCCUCCUCCCAAAAAGCAAGAGCUUGUUUAUGGCUGAGGAAUCGGCGGAUUGUCUGAAUGACACAUAUACAGAGCCCCCACGGAUUUCUGCACACUCUGGGUCUGUGCUGGUGGAACAUUGCCAAUCAGUUCUUAAUGAGGCACCUGUGUGUAAAUACAUGCUUGGUCUUCUCUGCAGAGAACUGAGGCUAAACUCUGUCCCUACUUCUGGUUUUGCCCUGUCAUGUCGUAACGAGGUGGGCCUUUUGAGGCCAUUUUAGUUUGAGUUCGAGCCAACCACCUCUGUUGGUUAGAUGAUGAAUAAAAAGGUUCUGAAGAAAA